UGUAACGAAACAGCAAACCUUGCGGUGGGAGCAGGAAGCCGGUGGGGGGAAGCGAUCUUCUCAUUUUUCCCAAGUACCCAUCUCUGCAUGCCUCCCUCUUCCCCUUUCCAGUUGCCAAAGCAGCUGAGUGGGAAGCAAAUCUGGAGCAGCAGGAACAGGACCAGGGAUCUGUAGAAGAGGUCAGUUUGAACUCUAGCCUUACUCCCUUCAAAGCCCACUAAAAUAAUUUUAAAUGCCAACAAGGACAUGUUCACGUCUGAUAACGCAGAUGCAGACCACGAAGUCAGACACUUUAAGAAAAGAAGGGUGGGCUGUAGGGACCUCCAAAUAAAGGGGGAGAAAUAUACUUUCUCCCCCUCCCCCAGUUUAAUGGACUUGAACAAAGUGCAGCAUAGCCACAUCUAGAGCCGAGAAGUCAUUGGUAGGUCAGGACAGCAACUUAAAAGCUUAUUUCCUAGAUCUUUUUUAAAAUAUCGACUUAACUCCUUUCCUUGUAGGCUUAUUUUGCCCCUACCUUGUGUUAGAACUUAUACCUCUUGAGCUGGGGAUAACAACUCUAACCUUGGCAUUUUAGCUCAAAAACAAUUCAGUAAAAAUACAAUACAGAAGGGCAUCCACGACAAUGCGGGGGCCCAGAAAGCACUUCCUAAGCCGCUGAUUAUUGACCCCUCCUGUAGUGAGGAAGGAGUGGCUUGGUGGCUCUGACUUUGGGCUAGUGGAGUGAAUUGGCAACUUUUAUUGAUUCCCAAUUGGCAGUCCACAUCAUACCAUUUUCUGAGGCCUGGGUCAAAGAAACCAUGAUCUCAUCUGGGCCUGUGGUAGGGGUUUGUUUAGUUUGAAGAAAAUAACUGGUAGGGGGCUGUAUAACAAAAACGCCAGGAAAACCGUUUUGGGGAGGUCCAUCCCUAGACAGAAAUCAGGUGAGAACGUUCACAGCCGAACUGGACUGGACCCGACUGUCUUUUCUUUAGUAUCAAGUACAAUUUGUAUGCGGCUUGUACAGAUCUGGUAAAUCAGAAGGCAGAUAGAUAGCACAGAUGGUUGGAGGUGUCGGGUCAGAUCACGCCACGCCUGAGUGCAGGGCAAAGCUCGUUCUGACGGAAAACCCUGAUAUUAUUUUCACAGAUCUUCACAGUUCACUCGAAAAAAAUAGCAGAGGGGAAGAAAAAAGCCCUGAAACCAUUUACAUCAUUUCUGUGAGAUUGCCAACCGCCUCAACGGAGAGGCUUUCUUUUCUAAGAGUUCAUUUUCUUGAAAUACGACAAGGCAGGGGCAAAAUAAAGAGGGCGAUGAAGAUAAUGACAAAGCAUAAACCUUCUUUCCCUUGGAGCGACUUCCGAAUCAGCCGGAAGGACAACUUUUAGAAAGAAACAUCGGAUACAAGGGCCCCGAACACGCAGGCGGAGGAGAAUCCGCGGUGCAGAAAAAGAGGGCCUCGGUGGCCGGGCAGGGAUGAAGCCGGACCCGGGAGGGCUGCGAUCCCGGAGCUUCUGGCCAGGGGAGGAAAGCACCCCCUUGCUCCAGUUUGCAGAGGUUUAUUUUCCCUCUCGGGGUGGUUACUUUGCCGGCUAUUGCUCGCGAAAUUGCUUGGCGCUCACCCUUAGCGCGCAGAAGAGGCGGUGGGGUCCGCGGAGACCUUACAGCCCGCGAGCCGAGCCGAGAGCCGACCCCGAUCCCAGCGCCUAGCUGCUGAGGUGGGAGAGGUUGUCCAUGCCCCAGGAGACCACACGUCUCCCUCUCGCCCUUUUACUGGACAGUUUGGAAGCGGCACAUUCGGGGAGAGCUGGUUUCUUACCCUUAAUCUUUGUGAGCAAGUGGACAGUCUAGGGGCCCCAUCCAGGAAAUGGGAAUAUUUAUCCCAUGGCCCAUUUCUUGGAUAAUAGUUCUGCAAAUAAUUAGAUGAGGGCGCUUUAGCUUCUGCGUGUCUGAGGCUCGCGGGCAACUGGAACUGAGAGUCUGAGUUGGCCUCGCGGGAGCCGCCAGAAGGGUGCGGGCUGCGUGUGGCAGAGUAGGAGCACUGUCUGGUGGCUUGGCAGGAAGGGACUGAGAAGUGCCUGGAGGUUGGGGACUACUAUCAGGAGAUCCAUCUUCGCCAUCGCAAGGGACUUGAUUUAAUUUUAUUAACCCAAAGGAAAUAGACUGCGCCAGGGCACCUUGGAAUCACUUAUUUGUUCACCAGCUUCACAAGGGGAAGGGACGAACAGGAAGAAGUAUGUGAGCCGAGCCCCCUGGGAAAGAGGGAAGCUCCACGGGAUUCCUUAGGAAUAACCCUCUUUUGGGGAAGGCGGUGACCCUCACCCCACCUUUAAGGUGUACUUCUCCCAAGUUUGCCAGACGAAAGCUGUGACUUCGGGCUGGCUUUUCUUAAUUUUACAGAAGGGUAUAUAUUUUUUUCUUUUACCAGUUUUGAGGUUUUGUGCCAACCCUCCAGGCAACCCCUCACUUCUUAUCCCACAUUUCAUUUUUCUUUUGCAUUUGACCGGGAAAUCGAGAAAGUACAGUGGCAGCCCUUGGCCUUGGGCCUGUCUGGGUGGUUUUGCAGCUUGCUACUGGUGGUUUGCAGCUAGUAGAUUGGGACAUGAGGUCUUGGACAAAGGCUCGGGUCUUGCCGGGAAUCCAUAGACGUCUACUCAGCUUUCUCUAGAGUUGCAUUUUGUGGGGCAAAUAUGGAGAAAAAAAUCAUGUAGAAGAUGAUGUCCAAGGGCUGGUUUUGUAGCUAACUGUUUCGUGCUGGAUUUAGGCAAAGUGCCCCCAGGGAAUUCUGAGGCUCAUGCCGGAAAUAUCUGGAGUUCAGUGUGGGACUUCUGCACAUAUGGGGAUCUCACUCCUCGCUCUGCCCCUACUGAUUUUCCUCUCUAGAGUAGAGGACAGGUGGAAUCCUGGUCACACCCUGCUCACAUUUGCCAGAGGAGAGCAGUGCUUAGAAGUCAAUACUUUCCUACCUCUGGGUUCCAAUCUUAUCUUUUCUUUGACUUUUCCUAAGUCAAAUGUCUUUUUUAAAAUGUUGUGUUUUUGUUUUUUUCUCACACAAUUUCACAUAAUCAGCUAUUUUAAGAAUGCGGUAAUUGAAUCCAUCUGAAUUCCUUGAUAAAGACAUUUGUGCUGCAUCUGAGAGUCACAGACUGGAAGACAAUGAGGUCCCCAGUCUUUUGUGUGAUUUGGACUUUGGAAGAGAUCUUGGUUUCCCUUUCCUGUGUCUCAAAGCCGAGUGUUGGUGGUGACAACUGGCUUUUAGUUUUAUAACUCUACUUCUAAAAAAGUAUAAAAUAAUCUAGAAAGUUUUAAAAGGCAUUUUUCCGAGUUUGAAAUUACACUAUUAAAAAUUUACACUUUCAAACAUUUAUUUAUUUGGCAUUCUGAUUUUCAGGUAUAUCAUAUGCAUAAAUAUAGAUGUGUGUUUGUUUAUGUGUUUGGUAGUACAGACCUUCAGAUUUUGGAAUGAAUUCAAUAUCCUACUUUUAAAGUACUACUAACUAUACUAAUAAACUGCCAAGGUAGAUUGCACUAUUUCAUGCAUUCCUCCCCUGCCAUUGUGCACCUUGUAACAAAGAACAGAGAAGGCUCUUUAAUUGUAUAUUUCUGAGAACAAACACCAUUUGAGCAAUGUUUGUAGAUUUCCUAGUGUUGUUAAAUUAAUUGGCAAAAAAGUAUUACAAUUAAAAUAUUGACCUAAUUUUAAGAGAUUAGUAUAUUUUGUUAUUAUUCUUCAUCAGCUAUUUUUAAAUGACAUUUUAAAGUGAUGCAGAAUUGUUUAUAUUGUUAAGUGGAGGAAAUUUGUAUAAGUUUAAAUUUGGGACAAUGUGCUACUUCACAGUGAUGAUUAAUUAGCCUAAUGUUUUCUUAAAAAAUGUUAGGCUACCUGUUCAACUGUGUUUUGACUUCUAGCUAGUGGUUGAUCCUAGGCACUUGGAUAAAAAUUUGUAUCUAAGCCAAAGAGUAGAUGACAAAUUAUACACUUUGUAAUAUAAACUGUGGUCUUAAAUUCAUUUUUCUCUUGUCUACUUCUUUAGGACAAGCCUAAAUGUUUACAGCACUAACCACAUCACUGCAUUACUUGCUUAGAGCUACAUAUCAGUGGGUUCUUGUCUGAAGGAUUAGUGCUAAAAAAUGUAGCCAGCUUGUCACUUAAAAACACUUUUCAUUAUUAGUAAUGAAACAUUUAUUGAAUGACUGAAAGAAUGAUUAAUUCAUGGUUCUCUAUUGGGACAUACUUUUUUCACAGCAGCAGGUUAUUUUUGACAAUUUUCAAAUCUAAGAUCGAAAUAUCCUUCUAAAAUACACAUAGAAACUUAAAAUUCAAUGAUGUGAAAGAAUGUAAGUUUGUUUAAUGUCCUCUCGGAUGCACCAAAUAUUAUUCACAUUAAACUGUAUGUGUCAUACAUUGUAUCAACUGUUUGUAUUACAUGUGUAGUAAAUCAUAAUUUCCUUCUAAGUACUAUAAAGUCAAAUAGAGGCAUCAGCCUUCAACAAAUACCUUAAAUUCUUUGAGUUGAUCCAGCUAGUUAGCAAAAAGUGCUUAUUAAAUAUUGCAUUAUAAAAAAUACAGUCACAUGACAUCUUACCCUUCAAAGCAGCAAUUCUCAACUGAGGGGAAUUUUGUUUCCCUCCCGCUGUUUCCCCACUUCCAGGGGACAUUUGUCAAUAUCUGGAGACAGUUUCGGUAGUCUCAGUUGGCAUCUAGUGGGUGCAGGCCAGAGAUGCUGCUAAACAUCUUAUGAUGAACAGAACAGUGGUCCCCCAGACCCCACAAUAACAAAGUCAAUAACACUGCUGUUAAGAAACCUUGACCCAAAGGAUCUUGCCCCAAAUGAUCAACAAGGCACAGACAUACAAAACCUGCUAAAAUUUGGUUUAUUGUGGAGUUGAAGCAUUUACAAAGGACUCAGAGCACUUUCAAUUUCAUCUUGGGUCUAGGCCAUGUUAAUAAAAUCUGUUCCUAAGAGCUUACUGUAAUUUUGUUUUUUCUUAAAAUUUACUGUAAAUGAUACUUAGGAUAACCAAAUACUUAUAAAGCUUGUAAAUAUCUGUGGGAAUGGUGGGGUUGCUUCUAUCUUGUUAGGAUCUAUGUUCUUUGAAUAAUUAGUGGGACAGAGAACAAUGGUUGAAAGUUAUUGUUCAGUGUCUCUCUAUUUUAUAAAUGAAUAAACUAUGAGGACCACAGAGGUUAAAUGAUUACCCAUAUUGCACAGUUAGUUAAUGGCAGAGAUAGGUUUAAAACAUAGACUCAAACUUGUAUCCAUUAUAUACCUUACUUUUUUUACUCAAGGAAAAUAAUUUAAUUCCAAUUGAGUUUGAGGGCAGUUCUGUAUCACACACAAAUAGUGGUUAAUGCCUGCCGUGUGUAAGGUCCAGUACUAUUUCAUGCUGUUGUGACUUUCAGAGUUUGGUGCACUCUAGUUCAAGGACCUCAGAGAGACUUACACUUCUGGGUCUUGUCAGGUGGUAUAACCCUUGCAAGCCCUAAAAACCCUUGAAUCAAAAAUGUGUCUCUGGGAUUUUUGUUGUUUUUUGAGCGGGGGUGGAAACUGGUGGAGUCUGGUGUUACUGAAGACCCUUCUCUGAGUCAGCACACUGUGUAUUGGCAGGAAAAAUGGAACUGAAUGCAGCCUCUAAGGAAAAGAGAUUGGACUUGAGGUGUCGUAAAGCUUGGUUUAAGUAAACAAAACCCUCUGAACUCUUUUGUCAGGUCUUCCAAAAGAAUAACAGUGAUGCUCACAAGCAUUUCUAUAAUUAACAAGCUGUCAACAUUUCUAUUACAACUACAGAAGUCUAUUACAGACCACAGAAUUGUCAUAAAUGUUUCUUUAGGUCUGAAAUGUUAGCCUUCAUCUUCUUUUCAGCCUAAGGGCAAUUUUUGAAACCAAUUUUGUUUCAAUCAUUUUGGAUCAGUUGUGUGGUAAUUUUGGAAGUGCAGAUGCUCUAGGCCCACCUAUUGAAAUAAAGAUUUUUAAAUGGAAACACAGAGAGGAGGCUGCUUAAGCCCCAGUGGGGACCAGCUGCAAAGCUCUGGCAGGGAAUUAUACAGGCAGACAGUGGGAGUAGAUUUAGAAAAAAAUUAAGGGACAGAGAAAUGAGUGCAUAUUUCCUUUAACAGCAGAUUUUUGUUCUCAGAUCUUUCAAACUAUGAAAUUUUAAUCUUUUUUUCUGUUUUAGUGUUUUAUCUGUUAUUACUUUCUCUGUUAUGCCUUGGUUUUGGUGAAAUUAAUGUAAGAUAAUAUGUCUUUACAGCUAUUAAAAUUGGGGGCUGAACUGAUUUUUUUGAAUUUUAGUAUUUAGUUUUUAUCUUUCAUUUAGUUGUUUUCUUUCUAUCCCUCUCAUCUCCUUUCUGUUUCUUUACCUUUUUAUCCUUUUUGUGGUCUCUGAAAGAUUUCUUAUUUCCCAAUGAUUGUAUUUCUCUGUGUUGUAAUAAUUCAUAUUUAUGUUCCCUUUUCUCCUUUGUGUUUCUUCUGACUCCAUUACUCCUUCCUAUUCCCCAUUGCUGAGGACCUCCUCACUAGACUAAGCCUUGUUAAAACUGUGAGAUAGAUAAAGAUACAAUACUCAAUUUCUGAAGGUAGAUGGGAGGAUGGGGAGUGGUUUUCAUAGAAAAGGGAAAUAGUGUCACUAUAAUGGUAUUUUAGGGCAAUGAUGUUUCUCAAACUAAACUUUAUAGAAGCAGAUAAAGCAGUAGAGCAAGGACUUCCAAUAUUUUAGGUUUAAAUCAUUGCAAUAACCACAUGAUUUUGGGCCCCCGUUUCCUUAUCUGAUAGCAUAAUUCUUAUCCUAUGGGAUAGAUGUAGGGAUUAAAUGAGAUUAUGAAUGACUGUUCCUUGCACAGUGCCUGACACAUAGUAAAUUCUCAACAAGUGUUAGUUCCCCUCUUGUGGGCAACUAUCCACUUAAUAUAUCAAUUAGGCCAUAUUGUCUUAAUGAUGUCUCACUUUCCAUCUUGUCCUGGGUCUCAUAAUCUUUUGAUGCCUGCCUUAGGUUUCUCGAAACUUUCCAAGCAAUAGGUUAUUUUGAAGUAGGCCUUCCUAUUCUGUGGACCACUGUUGUUGCAAUAAAUUAGUCUAAAGAAGUCAAUAGAUAGCUUACAUGAAAUUCCCCAAAUGCCCUCUGUAUUUGUUUCCUGUGGCUGCCAUAAGAAAUUGCCACAAACUGAGUGGCUUAAAACAACAGAAAUUUAUUCUCUCACAGUUCUGGAGGCAACAAGUUUGAAUCGAGGUGUUGACAGGGCGAUAUCCUCUCCAGAGGCUCUAGAGGAGCCUCUUCAUGCCCCUUCCAGCUUCUGGUGGCUGCUGGCAUUUCUUGUUUUGUGGCUGCAUCUCUCCAAUCUCUGCCUCCUUCUUUGCCUUACUUUCUCUCCUAUGUGUGGAUGUGUGGAUGUGAAAACUCUUUCUGCCUGUAUUUUAGAAGGAUGCAUGUGAUUGCUUUUUUUUUUUUUUUUUUUGGAGACAGGGUCUUGCUCUGUUGCCCAGGAUGGAGUGCAGUGGCACAAUCAUAGCUUACUGCAACCUCGAACUCCUGGCUCAAGCCAUCCUCACACCUCAGCCUUCUUAGUAUCUAGGACUACAGAUACAUGGCAUCACAUCUGGCUAAUUAAUAAUUUUUUGUGUGUGUAGAGACAGGGUCUCUCUAUAUUGCCUAGGGUGGUCUCAGACUCCUGGCCUCAAGUGACCCUCCUUCACCUGGCCCUAGACAGUCUAUUCUUAUUACACACACUCACACUUACACACACACACACAUACCUACAUGUACACACACAUUCCUCUCUAUUCUUUCCUCUGCUCUAGUUCAUUUGUUGCUAUUUGUGCUCUUUUCUCAUGUAUUGUCCUCAUCUGGAGUGCUAGGUUUUUUUCCUACUGGAAAUGUCUUUUUUUUUGUUCGUUUUCCUUCUUAUAAAAGCAAUACAUGGUCAUUGACAUAAAAAUCCAAGCACUAUGGUUAUAUAGAGUCAAAAAUGAGUUUCUCGUAGUACUAUUAUUAGAGAUAACUACUAUUAGUGCUAGGUGCAUAUCCUUAUGGACGUUUUUCUCUAUGCACAGAGACACACAUUUUUUCCCCUUUGAUGAAAGUAUUUAUAUUAUCCAUACUGUUUUAUAGCCUUUUCCUGAUAACAUUUCGUGAACAUUUUUCUUGACCAUAAAUAUGUUAUCAUUUUGAAGGUUACAUUGUGUUCUACAGCAUAAAUACCACAACUUAUUUAACCAGUCCCUAUUGAUGUUUAAAUUCCAUUUUUUCACCAUUAUAACAAUGAAGCAAGGAACAUGUUUAUGUAUUGUCCAGUUUUUUCCUUCAAAUUAUUGGAUGUGAAAUGGAUGGGUCAAAAGGUAUACACAUUAAACAAUUGAUACAUACUUCCAAAUUUCCAUCCAAAAAGACUUUUACCAAUUUUUACUUCUACCCACUCUGUAUAAGAGUGUCAUUCCCAGCCAGGCGUGGUGGCUGACACCUGUAAUCCCAGCACUUUGGGAGGCUGAGGUGGGUGGAUCACCUGAGGUCGGGAGUUCGAGACCAGCCUGACCGACAUGGUAAAACCCCAUCUCUACUAAAAAUACAAAAUUAUCCAGGUGUGGUGGCGCAUGCUUGUAAUCCCAGCUAUCUGGGUGGCUGAGGCAGGAGAAUCACUUGAACCCAGGAGGCAGAGGUUGUAGUGAGCCAAGAUCGCGCCAUUGCACUGCAGCCUGGGCAACAAGAGCGAAACUCAAUCUCAAAAAAAUAAAAAAUAAAAAAGGAGUGCUAGUCCCUCCUCACACUCUGGUCAUUAAUCUUCUUAUAAAUCUUUCCCAACUUGAUAGAUGAAAAAUAAUUUCUCAUUUUUUAAAAUGGGCAUUUCUUUGAUUAUUAAUGAGGUUAUACAUGUUAAUAUAUUUAUGGGUAAUUUGUAUUUAUUCUUUGGAGAAUUUUCCAUUGGGAUGUUUGUUCUUUCAAAAUCAUAUGUAAGGUCACUUCAAAUAUUAAGGAUAUAUAUUUUUUCUUGUCGUGUAUUGCCAAUAUUUCUUCACAGUUUUUCACUUGCCUUUUAACUUUAUCAAGUUGAUUGCCCUACAGGCAAUCACCUAUAGUUUUUACAUAGUUGAAUCUAUCAAAUCCAGUUCUGCCUUAGGGGCCAUACUUAGUAUUGCCAACCUUGCCAGUUAUAAAAAUAAUCUGUAUUUCCUUCUCCUACUAUUCUUAGAUUAAAAACAUUUUAAAACUGCUUAAUACUUCUGGAUUUAUUUUGUGGUCUUAUGUAAAUUUGAAAUCUAACAGCGUUGUUUUCUUCUUCAAAUCAUUUUCUAAUUCUACCACAAUUAUUUAUUGAUUGAUCUAUUCUUUUUCCACAGAUUUGAAACGCCACCUGUAUCACAUACUAAAUUUAUAUACAUAGAAAUUAUUCUGGAUCUUCUAUUCUGUUUCAUCGAUAUGUGUAUUUAUUCCUAUUGUUUCACAACUGCAGUUGAAGUACAUUUUAAUAUCUGAGAAAUGUAUCAUGAUUAUAUAUGUCAGUAUAAAGAAGUUUUGAAGCAGUACCAACUAAAAUACUCAGAAACACCCUUUUCACGUGAAUAUUAUGAGAAGAAAAGAGAACAUGAAGAAAUUCAAAGCAGAGUGUUGGCAUGUACUGAACAAUUAAAAAUGAAUGAAACAAUUUUUAUGAAAUUUCGAGUGCCUGCUCCCUUUCCAUCACUUACUAAAUGGACUUUAAACAUUGUUAAUUUGAGAUGUGAAACACAAGAUAUUCUUAAACAUGCCAGCAAUCUUACCAAAAGUUCAUCCGAAUUGAAGAAAGAAGUAGAUGAAAUGGAAAUAGAAAUUAAUUAUUUAAACCAGCAGAUAUCUAGGCAUAAUGAAACUAAGGCUCUUUCAGAAACUCUGGAAGAAAAGAACAAAAAUACAGAAAACAGAAAAGAACUGAAAGAAAGAAUUUUUGGAAAAGAUGAGCAUGUACUUACAUUGAAUAAAACUCAAAGCAGUCAAUUAUUUCUUCCUUAUGAAUCUCAGAAAUUAGUAAGACCAAUAAAGAUGCAUUCUUCAGAACCAAGAGUUGCAGAUAUAAAAGAAGAAAGUUCUGCGAAGCAGUCAAAGCUUGCCAAUAUUGACUUUAGACAAAAAGAAAAUGAUACACAGAUAUUUAAUGACUCUGCUGUGGAUAACCAUUCAAAAUGUUCACAUAUUACGACUAUCACAAGUUCACAAAAGUUUAUGCAAGUCAGAUUGUUAACCCCACAGAAACAAUCAAAUUCCAAUCAGUGGUCGGAAAAAGGGGAUAAAGAUGCUGAGUAUGGAGAUAAAGGGACAGUAAGACAAGUAAGAGAAUCAAAAUGUACUUCACAAGCUAUAUAUACUGAACAUUUUGGGAAGUCAGUAGAAAAUGAUAGUGAUGAAGUAGAAGAGAGAGCUGAGAAUUUUCCACGAACGUCUGAAAUUCCUAUAUUUUUAGGAACUCCCAAAGCUGUGAAAGCACCUGAGUCAUUGGAGAAAAUAAAAUUCCCUAAAACCCCCCCGUUCGAAAUUAACAGAAAUAGAAAUGCAGUACCUGAAGUUCAAACAGAAAAGGAAUCCCCUGGACUUUCUUUUCUUAUGAGUUAUACUUCUAGAUCACCUGGAUUGAAUUUAUUUGAUUCUUCUGUAUUUGAUACAGAAAUCUCAUCAGAUCAGUUUAAUGAACAUUAUUCUGCAAGAAAUCUAAAUCCUCUGUCAUCAGAGCAAGAGAUUGGAAACUUACUUGAGAAGCCAGAAGGAGAAGAUGGCUUUACAUUUUCUUUUCCAUCAGACACUUCAACUCAUACAUUUGGAGCUGGAAAAGAUGAUUUUAGUUUUCCAUUUUCAUUUGGACAGGGUCAAAAUUCAAUACCUUCUUCUUCUUUAAAAGGUUUUUCAUCUUCCUCACAAAAUACAACACAGUUUACUUUUUUUUGAGCUAGUCAUUAAUUCCUUAAAUUAUUUUACUGUUCUGUGUUCAUGAGGGCAUAAAUUUACAUUAUUGCUUAAAACAUGAAGACUGCUUUCUUUUAUUGAUUAAAGCAGUAAUGUUUACAUUAUUUGAUUAUAUUUAUUGAAAUAUUGAAAUACUGAAUAUUUUGGGUUUUGUGUGUGCUAUUAACUAAUCAUUAUUUAUUUUGGUUUUGAUUUUGCGAGCCGUGGUCAGGUAGAACUUUUAUUAAUCUUAAUAGAAUUUGAUGCUUUUUUCAUUACUCUUUAUUUAAAUAUUAAGCCUGCUUCUCCUUGGAACCUAAGGUUUUUUUCUGGAAGUAUUGUUGGUACUUUGAUAAGAACAAGAACUGCAGUAGUAACUCCAGAGUUAGUGCUGAAGCGUACUUUAGCUACUAAAAAUUUCUAUUAAAAUUAUUGGGUUUCACUUCUGCUUCACUAUGUAGUAUACAGAGUGGUACUGUAAUAAUAAUUUCAAAUAAUUUAUGUUAAUAACAAAAUCUGUGUUAUUUUCUUCUAAUAUAACACAUGGUACAAUUCUAAUUUUAUGAGUUAUGCUAAUGCUUUCAAUGGCUAAAAAUUAAAUGUAAAGGGCAAGAGUAAUUUCUGAAAAUUGGAUUGUUGUAUCAGUGGUGAUCCUGUUAAUAUUCUUUUUUGCUUAAAUAUUUUUUGAAGAACAUUUACAAUUUUGUCUCCUUCAAUAACAAAAAUUUCUUCUUUAUGUUUUGUGUUCAGUAUUUGUCAAUUAAUUAUAUAGCUUAAGUGAAGAUAUUUAAGAUUUGAUGAACUUCUGUAAACAUUUUGCUCAAUAUCAUUGUAUUUUGUGCUUUGUAAAUUAGCUGUACUGAGUUACCAAGUAAUAAAGGGUUUGACUCCA